CUUCAUGAUUAACUCCCCAAGGUCCUGCAUAUUUUCUCAAUGGGCCACCGCGCCCGGCCAGAAGAUUUUUAUGGUAAAAUUUUGUGAUGGGAAAACUCAUCCCGGAAAAUGUUGAGACCUGAUGCUGAGUCCUCAGCAGCUCAGAGAAUACGUACUUCUGUCCCAGGUCACCCAAACAUUGACCUGUGUCGGUUCCCCACUAGGAACAAAAUGUAACUGAGGACGUUGUCAGAUGCUUGUCCUCGUCACCCUGAGCUUGUUGGCUGCUAUCUAAUUCUUAUUCUUUCAUUUUCUUGCCCGCACGUUCUUGAUAGCAGAUCACUGACAACAGCCAUUGGAAGCUUAGGAAAAGGGUAUGUGCCGGGCGCGGUGGCUCACACCUGUAAUCCCAGCACUUUGGGAGGCUGAGGUGGGCGGAUCACGAGGUCAGGAGAUCGAGACCAUCCUGGCUAACACGGUGAAACCGUCUCUACUAAAACUACAAAAAUUAGCCGGGUGUGGUGGCGGUCGCCUGUAGUCCCAGCUACUCGGGAGGCUGAGGCAGGAGAGUGACGUGAACCCGAGAGGUAGAGCUUGCAGUAAGCAGAGAUCAUGCCACUGCACUCCAGCCUGGGCCAGAAUGAGACUCCGUCUCAAAAAAAAAAAAAAAAAAAGCAUGUGUAACGUGAAAAAAUGGACACUUUAGCCAUCGCCUGACUUUCUGUUGAAUUGGGAAAGAGCCUCCUCCCGUCCACAUGGGAUGGCCUUCCUGAUGUGGCUCUCCAAGACCAUCCCUGGAGGGCAUAAAACCUCACAAAUGCAUCAGGCCGUGUGCUGGGGAUGGGGCAUCGUCACGCCAGGUCUGACUAGGAAGGAGGAUGGGGAGGCAGGGCUGGGGGCUUUGAGGUCGAGGCGUGGCCGUGGAUUCCAGAAAGCCCCUUGGCUGGUGUGCGUGCCUGCCCAGCGGCAUCCGUGUAUCCUAACACCUGCCCUCCGUGUCCCUGCAUCUGCAGGCCAUGUCAAAGGACGCCCUGAAUCUGGCGCAGAUGCAGGAGCAGACGCUGCAGUUGGAGCAACAGUCCAAGCUCAAACAACUUGUCAAUGAGGAUUUACGGAAGCAGGAGGAGUCCGUGCAGAAGCACCAUCAGACCUUCUUGGAGUCCAUCAGGGCGGCUGGCACCUUGUUUGGGGAAGGAUUCCGUGCCUUUGUGACAGACCGGGACAAAGUGACAGCCACGGUGGCUGGGCUGACGCUGCUGGCUGUCGGGGUCUACUCAGCCAAGAAUGCGACAGCCGUCACUGGCCGCUACAUCGAGGCUCGGCUGGGGAAGCCGUCCCUAGUGAGGGAGACGUCCCGCAUCACGGUGCUUGAGGCGCUGCGGCACCCCAUCCAGCAGGUCAGCCGGCGGCUCCUCAGUCGACCCCAGGACGUGCUGGAGGGUGUUGUGCUUAGUCCCAGCCUGGAAGCACGGGUGCGCGACAUCGCCAUAAUGACAAGGAACAUCAAGAAGAACCGGGGCCUGUACAGGCACAUCCUGCUGUACGGGCCACCAGGCACCGGGAAGACGCUGUUUGCCAAGAAACUCGCCCUGCACUCAGGCAUGGACUACGCCAUCAUGACAGGCGGGGACGUGGCCCCCAUGGGGCGGGAAGGCGUGACCGCCAUGCACAAGCUCUUUGACUGGGCCAAUACCAGCCGGCGCGGCCUCCUGCUCUUUGUGGAUGAAGCGGACGCCUUCCUUCGGAAGCGAGCCACUGAGAAGAUAAGCGAGGACCUCAGGGCCACACUGAACGCCUUCCUGUACCGCACGGGCCAGCACAGCAACAAAUUCAUGCUGAUCCUGGCCAGCUGCCACCCCGAGCAGUUCGACUGGGCCAUCAAUGCCUGCAUCGACGUGAUGGUCCACUUCGACCUGCCAGGGCAGGAGGAGCGGGCGCGCCUGGUGAGAAUGUAUCUUAACGAGUAUGUUCUUAAGCCGGCCACAGAAGGAAAGCGGCGUCUGAAGCUGGCCCAGUUUGACUACGGGAGGAAGUGCUUAGAGAUCGCUCGGCUGACAGAGGGCAUGUCAUGCCGGAAGAUCGCACAGCUGGCCGUGUCCUGGCAGGCCACGGCGUAUGCCUCCAAGGACGGGGUCCUGACCGAGGCCAUGAUGGACGCCUGCGUGCAAGACUUUGUCCAGCAGCACCAGCAGAUGAUGCGCUGGCUGAAGGGGGAGAGGCCUGGGCCCGAGGACGAGCAACCCUCAUCCUGAGUCCAUGGGGAGACCACACCUCACGGAGCCUGGCCGCGGACCCCUCCCACCCCUGCCUUUGCGGCCCCGCACAUUUAGGAAAUACUCCCCGUAAUAAAGUCCCACGGGGGCCGCACCGCUGUGUCUAUUGGCUGACACGGGGCGGGGUUUGGGGCCCCCUAACGUCCCCCUGGGGUCAAAGGUGACAGAAAAGGCAGAAGCUGGGGCUUUCUGGAGGAUUUAACCACAGAGGGGUGGGCUUCACAGGAGGUGGCUGCCACGGCGGGGCCGGGUGCCCGUGCCCCAUCCUGAGGCCGUGCAUACGCGGGUGCCCCUUCGCCUCCCUCCCCUCCGCCAGAGCUGCCUGUGGCCAGACACACGGUGGAGGGAAGUGCACGCGAAACAGACACAGCGGCUUCAAAUAGAUGCCGCCCCUGCCCGCGCUUUGCAGCUAGUCCCUGCAAACCUUGAUGAUGGGGCUGGGCGCGGUGGCUCACGCCUGGAAUCUCAGCGAGGCCAAGGAGAGUGGAUCACCUGAGGUCGGGAGUUCCAGACCAGCCUGGCCAACAUGGUGAAACUCCAUCUCUCCUAAAAAAAAAAAAAAAAAAAAAAAAAAAAAAAAAAAAAUUAGCCGGCCGUGGUGGCAAGUGCCUGAAAUCCCAGGUACUCAGGAGGCUGAGGCAGGAGAAUCACUUGAGCCCGGGAAGUGGAGGUUGCACUGAGCUGAGACCAUGGAAUUGCACUGCAGCAUGGGCAACAAGAGUCAAACUCCCUCUAAAAAAAAAAAAAAAAAAAGGGCCAGGUGGCACAUGCCGGUGGUCCCAGCUUCUUGGCUUGGAGGCUGAGGUAGGAGGAUCGCCUGAGCAUGGGAGGCAGAGGUUGCAGUGAGCCAAGAUCGCACCAUUGCACUCCAGCCUGGAUGAUAGAGUGAGACUGUACCUCUAAAUAACCAAAACCUUGAUUACAGCCAUGGGGUGGGGGUGGGGGUCAGGGGCGUCUGACUAUGGCUGGGGAACUCAUUUGGUUUUUCUCCUCUCUUAUUUUUUUGGGUAGAGACAGGGUCCCUUUGUUGCCCAGGCUGGUCUCCAACUCCUGGGCUCAAGCAAUCCUCCUGCCUCGGCUUCCUAAAGUGUUGGGAUUACAGGCUUGAGCCACCGUGCCUGGUCUGUUUUUUUUUUUUUUUUGGCAAUAGAGUCUUGCUCGCCCAGGGUGGAGUGCAGUGGUGUGAUCUCGGCUCACUGCAACCUCCACCUUCAGGGUGUCAGGCCUCUGGGCCCAAGCUAAGCCAUCAUAUCUCCUGUGACCUGCACUUAUACAUCCAGAUGGCCUGAAGCAACUGAAGAUCCACAAAAUAAGUGAAAAGAGCCUUAACUGAUGACAUUCCACCAUUGUGAUUUGUUUCUGCCCCACCCUAGCUGAUCAAUGUACUUUGCAAUCUCCCCCACCCUUAAGAAGGUUCUUUGUCAUUCUCCCCACCCUUGAGAAUGUACUUUGUGAGAUCCAUCCCCUGCCCGCAAAACAUUGUCCCUAACUCCACCGCCUAUCCCAAAACCUGUAAGAACUAGUGAUAAUCCCACCACCCUUUGCUGACUCUCUUUUUGAACUCAGCCCGCCUGCACCCAGGUGAAAUAAACAGCCUUGUUGCUCACACAAA